AGCGACGCCGCCGGCCCGUCUCGCCGCGCUUCCCAGCGAGGCCGCCGGCGCGCCGAGGGCUGUGCUCGACCGCGAAUCCCGUGUGCAGUCGCCCCGCGCCCCGCGCGACCCUUCGGGUAAACUACGAACUGGGAGUUCUGAAGAAUGGGUAAAGACUUUCGUUACUAUUUCCAGCAUCCCUGGUCUCGCAUGAUUGUGGCUUACUUGGUGAUCUUCUUUAACUUCUUAAUAUUUGCGGAGGACCCAGUUUCUCAUAGCCAAACAGAAGCCAAUGUUAUUGUUGUUGGAAACUGUUUUUCAUUUGUUACAAAUAAAUACCCUAGAGGAGUUGGCUGGAGGAUUUUGAAGGUGCUUCUAUGGCUACUUGCCAUUCUCACAGGACUAAUAGCUGGCAAAUUUCUGUUCCAUCAGCGUUUGUUUGGUCAGUUGCUCCGAUUAAAAAUGUUUCGAGAAGAUCAUGGGUCGUGGAUGACAAUGUUCUUCAGCACAAUUCUCUUUCUCUUCAUAUUUUCUCACAUAUACAACACGAUUCUUCUAAUGGAUGGGAACAUGGGAGCAUAUAUCAUUACAGACUAUAUGGGCAUCCGAAAUGAAAGUUUCAUGAAAUUAGCUGCAGUAGGGACCUGGAUGGGGGACUUUGUCACAGCUUGGAUGGUCACUGAUAUGAUGCUUCAGGACAAACCCUAUCCUGACUGGGGAAAAUCAGCAAGAGCUUUCUGGAAGAAAGGAAAUGUUAGGAUCACUUUAUUCUGGACAGUUCUUUUUACUCUGACGUCUGUGGUUGUACUUGUGAUUACAACGGACUGGAUCAGCUGGGACAAGCUGAAUCGGGGAUUUUUGCCCAGUGAUGAAGUUUCCAGAGCAUUCCUUGCUUCUUUUAUCUUGGUCUUUGACCUUCUUAUUGUGAUGCAGGACUGGGAAUUCCCACAUUUCAUGGGAGAUGUUGAUGUAAAUCUCCCUGGUUUGCACACCCCUCACAUGCAGUUCAAGAUUCCUUUCUUCCAGAAAAUCUUCAAGGAGGAAUAUCGUAUUCACAUAACAGAAUCCUUAUCCAGGUAUCAAGACUGGCCAUGAAGAUGUUUCCCUUGACGUGAUGAGCCCUAUUCUCAUCCCUGGAAUGGAAAUUCUUCACAGGGUUUCGAAGAGGACCAAAGAAGACUGUAUAUAUGUGAAAGCAUGCAGGUAGCUGCAACAAGUCAUGCAGAUGUGAGGUGAAUAUGACAGGCAUGGGCUCCAGUCCCCUCUAGUGCCCAGCUUUCAACAGAACCCCCUUGGCUUCUUCCAAGUUGAUGCUGCCAUUAAACAUGGUUAGGCCAUUUGCUCCCAAUUUUCUGUCCCUGUUGGUUGCUUUGAACUCUACAAGCUGCAAUGUAAUCCCUUUUCACUUGUAACAGAAGUUCAGAUCCCUUAGUUUAAAGCAAGCAGCUAUAUUGUGUGAAAUCAAUGGUCAUAAUCCCUUGGAGCUGCUGGGCCAAACUUAUUCCUCAAGGUUUCCUAGGCUCUAGAGUUCUAAAUUAUUUCCUUCUUUUUAUGAUUUCUUUACUAGCUUCUCUUAUCAGGACACUCUCAUCUUGCCAGUAAUCCACCACCUUUCAUAAAUCCUGAAGUGAAAGUGCUUGUGUCUUCAGCAUUUAAAGAAAGCUGACACAUGCACCUGAGCCCCUGCACUUUAGGAUCUUCCAGCUGUAUUUGGAUGAAGUUGAGGUAGCCACUUCUGAAUUGGGAUGUCACUCUAGCCUUGCCUUUUAGAAAGCUCACCUUGGCAGCCUGUGGAAUCAGGGCAACACUUCAGCCAAGCCACAGUGCUUUGUAGAAUAAAAUUUUAAAACAGUGUCAGGGUUUUCCAUUCACCAUAUAGACUUAUUUGCUUUGAAUACAUCAUUUUAUCUGGAUAGCAGUUGACUUCAACCAAACCACACUAGAAAAUAUCUGCAUUUAAAAACAGUUACUCUUGACUGAAACAAAAUGUGUAAGAUGAGACGAAGAGCAAUGGCCAUAUCAGGAAAGAUAACUCUAACAAUUACUCUUCAAGCUUGAUAACCAUGAAAUUACUAUAAAAUUAUCUUUGAACAAAUUAUAAUGUUUUUGCAUUUGAAGCACAACAUGUUGAACUUCAAAUACACUAGAAAACUCAGAGGCUCUGUCAUUUACAUAUCCAAAUGGUCUCCAAAAUGAAUAGAUUUUAUUUACUUCUGUCUCCUAUAAUUGGUCCACUAUCCUAUUCCCCAUCAUUAUCACUACUGCCAUGCUGCAAUCUCAUAUUCUAUUCCAAAGAUGACUGCAAUUAAUCUUAAUUGGUCUUCCUGGCUCUCACCUUUUCCAGUGCUAUCUAUUCUCCACACUUGUACCAGAAUAAUAUUUCUGAAGUGUAAAUCCGAUUGUAACACUUCACACUUUCAGUGGCCAGUUAUUGCCCAGCAGUGGUUUUCAAAAGUAUUGUGUACAAGUCCAAAAUCCCACUGGCUUAACACAAUAAAAAUCAAUUCCUUGCUCAUAUGGCCACUGAACUGGGUGUUCACUGGGUAGCCUUACAUACAAUGACUCAGGGACUCAGACAUGUUUCAGCAAGAGGUUCUUUGACUUUCUAGGGUCUUACAGUCUUCAGCAUAUUCAGCAGGCUGGUGAUGAAGGAGAGCAGGUGAGGAAGAUGCUGUAAGAAUUUUCAGGAAUAGACUUGGAAGUGGCAUAUAUCACUUCUUGCAUUCCAUUGGCCAGAACUCAGUUACAGCCUGUGCCUAACUGCAAGGAAUGCUAGGAAAUGCUGUUCAGCUCUAUGCCCACAAAGGACAUGGAACAAGUUUCAGGAGUUUCUGGUCAGAAGAGCAUUUGCAAAAUAUGCCCAGCCAUGCCUCACACUUGGAAGUACAUUCAGUGGGUUUGGGAUGGAGCUAGAGCUGAGCUGAGUUUUUAAAGUUCCAUAGGUGAUUCUCUUACAAACAUCAAUUUGAGAACCACUAAUAAAAUGCAUAUUACUGCCUGGCACUCAAGACUGUAUGCCAGCUUCUCUGGUUUUCUCUCCCCUGUCCAGUGACUUCUAACCCUGCAGCCAUGUUGAACUACUGACAGCUCUCCAUUGCAUCACUUGUACCACUCAACUCUGCUUUUGCUCAGUGUCUUCUGUUUGGAAUCCGCUUUUCCACCAUAACCAGCAAGACCAAUUCAAAUAUCAUCUCUUUUAUUAAGUCUUUCUUCAUCUUCCAAAAUAAAAUGUACUGCCCCUCUCUUGUGUUCCUAUAUGACCUACCUUUUAUCUAUUAUAGUAUCUUUAGCAUUUCUUCCACUAUAUGUUUAUAUAUCUGUGUCUCCUAUUAGAUUAUAAACAUUUUGAUCCUGCCUAUAAUGAUGACUUGGUGUGGGGGGGAGGAAUUAAUUAGCUUUAUAGUUUCUGACUCAAUAAAAUUUGACUGAAUAACUACAUAUUAAGUGAAAUAAUGUACUUAGAAUUGAUUCAUUUAGGCCGGGUGCGGUGGCUCAAGCCUGUAAUCCCAGCAAUUUGGGAGGCCAAGGCAGGCAGAUCACUUAAGGUCAGGAGUUCGAGACCAGCCUAGCCAACAUGGUGAAACUCUGUCUCUACUGAAAAUAUAAAAAUUAGCCUGGUGUGGUGGCGGGCACCUGUAAUCCCAGAUACUCAGGAGGCUGAGGGAGGAGAAUCACUUGAACCAGGGAGGCGGAGGUUGCAGUGAGCCGAGAUUGUGCCUUUGCACUCCAGCCUGGGCAACAGAGUGAGACUCCAAAAAAAAAAAAAAAAGAAAGAAAAGAAAAAGAAUUGACUCAUUUAUGUAGCAUAAUAUUCUCAAAUUAUCUGAUCCUCUCCAUGAUAGAGGACUCCAUGACUCUGCCAGUCAAAUCCUUUCAGUUAAGAGGGAGGCAGGAUUAUUUCUUACAUUCAAUAUGGGAAAUGAGGGGUAAGAAUAGAAAAUUUAAAAAAUCCAAUUUAAAGCGAGUAUCCCAGUUGAGCCAGAAAAACUUGAACAAAACUAUCAAGUAAGGGAGGCCCACGGUAGGGAGUGAGAGCAAACCAGGACAAAGCAUGAGAGAGUUAAAACAAAGAGCAGCCAGUCAGAGGGGGCAGCUAGAAGUCCCCUGCACUAAUUUCUGAAACAAGAGUGCAAUAUCCUCACCUGACUCUUCAGUUUCUUCUUCUACUAGAGCUUUUCAUGAGUGAAUUGACUGUGAUUGAUGGGAAGGCAGUUAUGUGAUGACUGACUCUGUAUCUUGAGAUGCCAGUCUUUUAAAAGAAAGGAAAUAUAAUGUCCCCAUUCUUUAUGUUUUUCUACAGUUCAUAUCUCUAAGUGCAGACCCAUAGCACUUAGUAAGUUUACAGGCAGGACCAGACAGAAUGAAAUUGAGAUGAUGAAACAGGUUUGCAUUUUACAUGUUGCUCUCUGAAAGCCACAACUGGAAAAUAAACACAAGUCGGAAGCUCUAAAACUCGGACGAACUGUGAUUAUAGCUGUACUUUUAUAACUGGUAUCUCAGAACUCCCUAGAAGCUUAUUUACAUGUUGAAAACAUCAAUUAUUCCUCCCAUUUGAAAUACAUAGUUCUUGUAAUCAAUUGCUUUGAGUCAAUGUUUAGAAUUAUUCAUGAAAGAGUUAUAUUUUAAUGGCAUUUGAUGAGAACCAGCAGCAGCAUCCAUUAAUUUGAUUAGUUGUUUAUGGGCUGGAAGAGAAGCCUGGCACCUAGCCCUAAGCAAAUCAAUUGUGUGAGGUCUAAGCAUAAGUAUCCAUCCAAGCCAGCCUUGCCAGCCAGGAUUCUACACAGAGUGACAACAGUGGAGGGAGGGCAAAACGUUAGACAAGAAGUGUCUUACGGCCCCUCUUUCUGCCUGCUUGGCAUUUUACCAUCAGUUACCUCUUAUCUAAAGGCAGUGAGUGUAAGCUGUUUUUCUACUCCACCCUACUCCGGCCCCAUACCCUGUUGUCCUUUCUGAAGGACAGAGUAGAGGGAUUUCUGUGGGUGGUUGUUUUUUUUUUUUGUUUGUUUUGUUUUGGUUUUUUUUUUAAACCUAAGGACUUAAAUAUGUAUCAUCAUCCAAGCCUGAAAACAAAUAAAUCUGGACAUUGAAGAAAACAGGAGCAAGAGCCAGGGGCCCAAUUCCACUGCAGGUUCCUCUGUUUGAAAGGGUUGAGGAGUAGCUGCCAAAGAAGGCAGAAGAGCCCAUGAUGCAAGGGAUCCAAUAUGGAGGGAAGUGUAGCAGCAGACACUGCUGGAGCUGGCAGGGUGUUGUCAUUGUCCCAGAGAAAUCUGUCCAGUUUGAAGCAGGAAGCAUUCCUGGGAGAAGCCAAAGGAAAGCCAUACAGACAGCCCAAGCUGGGACGUCAACCAGUUUGCAUUUUGUGAUUGACCAGUCACUUGGCCUCCAAUCAAAUGGUCUCGGGUUUUGGGCAGGGUACCGGUAGAAAAUGGACUGCAGACAAGAGACCAGGCUGUAUUCUAGUCCCAACCACCAGACACACCAUAUGGGGGAAAGUAACACCUCAGUGCCCACCCCACCCCCACACAGGAGGAGCUGGCUCCUGAGAACAGGCCUAACUGCUGGGGGCAGGCUACUGGGACACCGCUGGAUUUUGGUAGGAGUCACUCAGUGAUUGAACAAAGCCGAAUCCACAGACCUAAGGAUGCUCCUGCACAAAAAACCAACUGAAAUAAUGCCAAAGAAUAAUGCUUUGCUAAGGCAGGGAAGAUUGCAUUUGUUUUUAUAACAGUCUACCUUCAAAAAAAGGUAGUCCUUUCUAUAGCUAUAAUUAAGUCAUUAUUUGUGUCAUUAUGAGUUUUAAGUGUAUCUUUCCCUCUAGUUAUUUGUAUGGCUCAAUCCUGUAUAUCUAGUGCCUCUCUCAGGAUAUAUGAUAAAUGUUUGUGAGGAUGGAUAUGUUAAUUAGCUUGAUUUAAUUAUUCCACAUUUGUAUUACAAAAUCAUAGCAUCAUUUUGUACUCUAUAAAUACAUACAACUAUAACUUGUCUAUUUACAAUAAACUUUUUAUAACAAGGA